UUUUUUUUUUUUCAGAUGAGUCUCACUCUGUUGCCCAGGCUGGAGUGCCGUGCUGCGCUCUCAGCUCACUGCAACCUCCGCCUCCCGGGUUCACGCAGUUCUCCUGCCUCAGCCUCCCAAGUAGCUGGGACUACAGGCAUGUACCACUACACCUGGCAAACUUUGUAUUUUUAGUAGAGACAGGGUUUCACCAUGUUGGCCAGGCUGGUCUCGAACUCCUGACCUCAGGUGAUCCACCCAUCUCGGCCUCAUGGGAUUACAGGCGUGAGCCACUGCGCCCAUCCAGAGAAACUGUAUAUAAUUGGCAAAUGUCUCUGCAUAAAAGACUCUUCCUAAUUGCUGCAACUGCUGGCCCAGGUCUGGGACAGGGAGAAUUGUAUUUGUGGGUCCCAAAAGUCCUCUUGAGUGUGAAGUGUCUUUGCUCUUCCUGUUGGGAAGCCCCACGUUCGUUAGCAGCUCCUGCCCCCUGGGCUCACUUCUGCAAAGCAAGCCUGCCUCUAUUUCUGCUCAAGUGCAGUGUUCCAGGAGAACCUGACUGCAUGUCCCAGCUCUGCCAGCUCUCAGUGGUGGGUUCUUGGCCACCUGUAGCUUCAUUCUCCCAUCUGCCAAUGAGGGUGGUCCUACCUAGCACAGCAAUGGUGGGGCAGUCGAGCACCGGGCAGAGUAGGUGCUCAGUGAAUGAAAUACUGUAAUUAUUAACACAUGCCAUGGACAGCAGUGCAGGCCUGCGGGAUCAGGUGCAGAAGGAAGUUAACCCAGUGAAUUCCACACCUGGUAAUCCACACUGUGUUCUCAGGUUAAAGAAGCAGGAGGAAGCAGGCAUUGAGUCAAAUUGGUGGCUGUUUGCUAAGUGUGGGGUUUUACUGAAGGCAGCACCUGCUUCUGCAGCACAGCUGGUCUGAAAAGCCAGGUUGCUCCUUGUGAGGGCUUAGGGGUCGGUUUUAACAGUCACUCCAAGCAGGCACAGGGAGAAGAUGCUGUCCUCUUCUGGCAGCCUGGCUGGUCAUAACUCCAUGCAGGAAGCUCAUCUUGUGUGCUGAUAACAGAAAAGAAAUGGAAGAUUGGAUUGCAGCAUUAAAGACUGUGCAGAACAGGGAGCACUUUGAGCCCACCCAGUACAGCAUGGACCACUUCUCAGGGAUGCACAAUUGGUACGCCUGUUCCCACGCGAGGCCGACCUACUGCAAUGUGUGCCGUGAGGCUCUGUCUGGGGUCACGUCGCACGGGCUGUCCUGCGAGGUGUGCAAAUUUAAGGCCCACAAGCGCUGUGCUGUGCGUGCAACCAAUAACUGCAAGUGGACCACACUGGCCUCGAUCGGGAAGGACAUCAUUGAAGAUGCAGAUGGGAUUGCAAUGCCCCACCAGUGGUUGGAAGGAAACCUACCUGUGAGCGCCAAGUGCACUGUGUGCGACAAGACCUGUGGCAGUGUGCUGCGCCUGCAGGACUGGCGCUGCCUCUGGUGCAAGGCCAUGGUUCACACAUCGUGUAAAGAAUCCUUGCUGACCAAGUGCCCACUUGGCCUGUGCAAAGUGUCAGUCAUCCCACCCACGGCUCUCAACAGCAUCGACUCCGAUGGGUUCUGGAAGGCCAGCUGUCCUCCUUCUUGCACAAGCCCACUGUUGGUCUUCGUCAAUUCAAAAAGUGGGGACAACCAGGGUGUGAAGUUCCUCAGAAGAUUCAAACAGCUACUAAACCCCGCCCAGGUCUUCGACCUCAUGAACGGAGGCCCACACCUCGGCUUACGGUUAUUCCAGAAGUUUGACACAUUCCGGAUUCUGGUUUGUGGCGGGGAUGGAAGUGUUGGCUGGGUCCUCUCCGAAAUCGACAGCCUCAACCUUCAUAAACAGUGUCAGCUGGGAGUGCUGCCGCUCGGCACAGGGAACGACUUGGCCCGAGUACUGGGCUGGGGCUCAGCCUGCGAUGACGACACCCAGCUCCCCCAGAUCUUGGAGAAGUUGGAGAGAGCCAGCACCAAGAUGCUGGACAGGUGGAGCGUCAUGGCAUACGAGGCCAAGCUCCCCCGGCAGGCCUCCUCCUCUACCGUCACCGAAGACUUCAGCGAGGAUUCCGAGGUACAGCAGAUUCUCUUCUAUGAAGACUCGGUUGCAGCCCACCUUUCUAAAAUCCUCACCUCGGACCAGCACUCGGUGGUCAUCUCCUCGGCCAAAGUGCUCUGUGAGACGGUGAAGGACUUCGUGGCACGGGUGGGGAAGGCCUAUGAGAAGACGACCGAGAGCUCGGAGGAGUCAGAGGUCAUGGCCAAGAAGUGCUCUGUCCUGAAAGAGAAGCUGGAUUCCCUUCUCAAGACCUUGGACGAUGAGUCCCAGGCCUCGUCCUCUCUGCCCAACCCGCCCCCCACCAUUGCCGAGGAGGCUGAAGAUGGAGAUGGGUCGGGCAGCAUCUGCGGUUCCACCGGAGACCGCUUGGUGGCAUCAGCUUGCCCGGCCCGGCCGCAGAUAUUCCGGCCUCGAGAACAGCUCAUGCUGAGAGCCAACAGCCUGAAGAAAGCAAUUCGUCAGAUCAUAGAACACACAGAAAAAGCUGUCGAUGAGCAGAAUGCCCAGACCCAGGAGCAGGAGGGCUUCGUCCUGGGCCUCUCUGAGUCAGAGGAGAAGAUGGACCACAGAGUGUGCCCACCACUGUCCCACAGCGAGAGCUUCGGGGUCCCCAAGGGGAGGAGCCAGCGCAAAGUGUCGAAAUCUCCGUGUGAAAAGCUGAUCAGCAAAGGGAGUCUGUCCCUAGGCAGUUCUGCUUCCCUUCCGCCCCAGCCGGGAAGCCGGGACGGCCUGCCUGCGCUCAACACCAAGAUCCUGUACCCAAAUGUCCGGGCUGGAAUGUCUGGUUCCUUACCCGGUGGCUCAGUCAUCAGUCGCCUGUUAAUUAAUGCUGAUCCCUUCAACUCUGAACCAGAAACCCUAGAGUAUUACACGGAGAAAUGUGUCAUGAACAACUAUUUUGGCAUUGGCCUGGAUGCGAAGAUAUCCCUGGACUUUAACAACAAGCGCGAUGAGCACCCAGAGAAGUGCAGGAGCCGAACCAAGAACAUGAUGUGGUAUGGAGUUCUUGGAACCAAAGAGUUGCUGCACAGAACCUACAAGAACCUGGAGCAAAAGGUCUUGCUGGAGUGUGACGGGCGACCCAUCCCACUCCCCAGUCUUCAGGGAAUUGCUGUCCUUAACAUUCCCAGCUAUGCCGGAGGAACCAACUUCUGGGGGGGUACCAAGGAAGAUGAUACUUUCGCAGCUCCAUCAUUCGAUGACAAGAUUCUGGAGGUGGUCGCCGUGUUCGGCAGCAUGCAGAUGGCCGUCUCUCGAGUCAUCAGGCUACAGCAUCAUCGGAUCGCCCAGUGUCGCACGGUGAAGAUCUCCAUCCUUGGGGAUGAGGGCGUGCCUGUGCAGGUGGACGGAGAGGCCUGGGUCCAGCCGCCAGGGUACAUUCGGAUUGUCCACAAGAACCGGGCACAGACACUGACCAGAGACAGGGCAUUUGAGAGCACCCUGAAGUCCUGGGAAGACAAGCAGAAGUGCGAGCUGCCCCGCCCUCCAUCCUGUUCCCUGCACCCGGAGAUGCUGUCCGAGGAGGAGGCCACCCAGAUGGACCAGUUUGGGCAGGCAGCAGGGGUCCUCAUUCACAGUAUCCGAGAAAUAGCUCAGUCUCACCGGGACAUGGAGCAGGAACUGGCCCACGCCGUCAAUGCCAGCUCCAAGUCCAUGGACCGUGUGUAUGGCAAGCCCAGAACCACAGAGGGGCUCAACUGCAGCUUCGUCCUGGAAAUGGUGAAUAACUUCAGAGCUCUGCGCAGUGAGACGGAGCUGCUGCUGUCUGGGAAGAUGGCCCUGCAGCUGGAUCCGCCUCAGAAGGAGCAGCUGGGGAGUGCUCUUGCCGAGAUGGACCGACAGCUCAGGAGGCUGGCAGACACCCCGUGGCUCUGCCAGUCCGCAGAGCCCGGCGACGAAGAGAGUGUGAUGCUGGAUCUUGCCAAGCGCAGUCGCAGUGGUAAAUUCCGCCUCGUGACCAAGUUUAAAAAGGAGAAAAACAACAAGAACAAAGAAGCUCACAGUAGCCUGGGAGCCCCGGUUCACCUCUGGGGGACAGAGGAGGUUGCUGCCUGGCUGGAGCACCUCAGUCUCUGUGAGUAUAAGGACAUCUUCACACGGCACGACAUCCGGGGCUCUGAGCUCCUGCACCUGGAGCGGAGGGACCUCAAGGACCUGGGCGUGACCAAGGUGGGCCACAUGAAGAGGAUCCUGUGUGGCAUCAAGGAGCUGAGCCGCAGCGCCCCCGCCGUCGAGGCCUAGCCUCUGUCCUCUCAGCCUGUGGCCUCCACAUCCCCGCCGCCGAGGCCUAGCCUCCGCCCUCUCAGCCUGUGGCCUCUGCGCCUCCUGCCACUGAGGCCCUGGGCAGAUGCUGCAGCCCGCCCCCUUCUCAUGGUGCUACUUCCUCUGUCAGCUACAGAAAGCCUCCGUGACACCGUCCACCAGAGCUCUGGGGUCUCGAACAUAACAACACAGCUACCUUUGAAACAACACUUUCUCCAGCUCAGAGUCACCUGGGGCACAUGUGUCACGGCCACUCAGCUCUCGCCCGCCUGUGCUGUGGGCCAGGGAAUCCAGCGGCGUCUGGCCUCCUGGGCACUGCUUGCCUGGCCUCGUGCUUGGAUUGUCCCGGGGGCUCCUCUCCGUGUGUCCUUCUGUGGCCGCACCGUGUGGCUCCGCCUCCUGGCCCCCAGCCAGUUCUCAGAAACGUGGCUGGGGCCCAGCACAGCAGCCUGCAAGGGCCCCUGUUUGUUGAUGCAGCUUUUGUUGAACAAAAAUCGUGCUCUUUCCUGGUUUGAAAGUAGCAUGGAUGUUUCCAGUCUUGUUGAUUGUAAUUUGACGUGAAGAGAAAAAAAAAUUCCUCCUGCGUGAGCCAAGGCAGCGGGUGCUGUUUCCCAGGCGGGGAGCCCCUCCCUGGGUGUCACAGGGCCUGUGCUCCUCCCUCCUCCAUCCUCUCUCCUCCCGCUCCUCCCUCCCCCCACUGUGGGCUGGGGACGCCUGCCCUUCUGUCUCCGGACGCUCUAGGCGAGUUCAGCUUGGGGUGUGAGUGAGACAGCUUGCCAGCUGCAUCCCUGCAGACAGAGGAUGUGUGUCCACAUGAGUGUUUCUGUGUGGGAAAUGCUUCCUGGCUCUGGGAAACUUUUUCUGCCCAUUCUGUGGUUCCCAGGGAGCGUGGCCCUGGUGGGCCAGGGGUGGUUUGACCUCUUCAGCCCGUCCGGUGGCCUGGAGGCCGGAGGCUCUCCUGAGUGUCUGCCCCUGCAGUGGCUUCUUGUCGCCUGCUGCUGGGCGUGAUGUCGCUGGAGGUGCUGGCAGGGACUCUGAUUUGGUGGUCCGCGCUGCCCCUGCCCUGCCUCUGUCCUGGCUCUGAACUAGUAGAUGAUGGUGCCAGAGGGCAGGGAGCUCGCCUGGGGAGAGGGCUGUGCCCCGUAGGGACAGUGCCCAGGUGAAGGAUGCCCCUGGUCCUCCAGGGCACUGACUUUGCCCUUUUUUCCCGUUGAUAGUCAUGGCUCAGAGGUGCUUGUAAAUGUCUUGGGAAGAGGUUUCUGUAACCCCUGCCCUGGUGUGAGGAGGAAAUGGCUCUGGCCUGGCUGCCUGGCCGUGGCUUCUCUUUGGCUCCCAAAGAGAAGGACAGUGUUGGGAGUAUCUGCCGUGGCUUCUCUUUGGCUCCCAAAGAGAAGGACAGUGUUGGGAGUAUCUGCCGGCGCUGUCCAGGUCCUUUAGUCAGCGUCACUCCAUCUGAUGUGCAGAAGCUGGGCUGCACCUGCGGGGGUGGGCAUAGACCGGGCUGGGUCUGCAGCAGCCCCUGGUCCUGAGCAGGCGGCAGUGAACAGCACUGGCCCACCUCCCACUCACAGCCCCUCUGUCCCCUCUGCAGUGCACCCAGGUGGGCCCCUCUGCGUGCCUUUGGGUGCUCCCCUCUCGUGGUCGUUCUGGCCCGAGGCCCUUAGAGUAUGGAGGCUGAGCCAGGCCUUGGGUUUCCCCAGCACAGCCUCCUGUCGCUGCAUGCGACGUGUUGGGAUUUUUGGAUGAAAGACUCUCCCACGCUCUGUUGGUGGACUUAGCUGCCUCACUGGAAGUGAUGUGGGUGGAAGGUGGUUGUAUGUUACCUUUUCCACCUCUCAUUGUUUUCCCCAGAACAUUGUAGAUGGGGGUUGGCAGAGGGAGAAAUAAGCCAGCCACGGCAGUCGCUUGGUUUCCCAGGUGGAAUGGGCUAACACAGGAGAUGAUGGGAACCUGUCCCGCAGUCCCUGCAUGACCAUUGGCCCUGCUGGCCUGGCGAUGUGGGCAUCCUGGGGUUCUUAGGGUCCCAGAACAAGCCCCAGGCAAGCUGGAACUUGGGUGGGGAGGGGACAUGAGGAGGAUAAACAGCUGACUGUGGCUUCAAGGACAUCAGGGCCACCCCAAGUCCUCAGUGUCCUACUCCUGGCAAGGAGUUGGGUUUGGAUCAAAAGUGUUUAAAAUUAAUAUGUUGUCAGUGAUUAGAACAACACUGUUUACAUAAAAACCAUUUUUCUAAUUCUAACAAGUUAGAAUGUGAGGAAGGAAUGAACAUGAGUGUUUAGGAACCUGCCCUUUGGUGCUGGGCUGGCGUCCCGCACUGGGGUGUCCUCGCUGUCUGGGGGCUGCUCUGCUGCCCCGGCCCAGGUCCCCUUGUGGUGUUGCCAGACGGGCCUCAUGGUCUGCUGUGCAGAGAGAGGCAGGAAGGAUCCCUGAAGAGUCUUGGAGAAAAGGUUCUGUGCCCUCAGGUGGGGCUUACCCCCUCGUAUUUAUAAUCUUAAUUUAUAUAGUGACCACCGUGGAAACAAACGCCUCUUGUAUUGUCAUGUACAUAGUCCAUACCUGAGUGCUGUACAUAAGUUGUUCUGUGUAUAAAUAAAACAAGCCUGUUUUUGAUCUUCCA